AGCAGGAAGCUCGCGCCGCCGUCGCCGCCGCCGCUCAGCUUCCCCGGGCGCGUCCAGGACCCGCUGCGCCAGGCGCGCCGUCCCCGGACCCGGCGUGCGUCCCUACGAGGAAAGGGACCCCGCCGCUCGAGCCGCCUCCGCCAGCCCCACUGCGAGGGGUCCCAGAGCCAGCCGCGCCCGCCCUCGCCCCCGGCCCCGCAGCCUUCCCGCCCUGCGCGCCAUGAACGCCCCCGAGCGGCAGCCCCAACCCGACGGCGGGGACGCCCCAGGCCACGAGCCUGGGGGCAGCCCCCAAGACGAGCUUGACUUCUCCAUCCUCUUCGACUAUGAGUAUUUGAAUCCGAACGAAGAAGAGCCGAAUGCACAUAAGGUCGCCAGCCCACCCUCCGGACCCGCAUACCCCGAUGAUGUCCUGGACUAUGGCCUCAAGCCAUACAGCCCCCUUGCUAGUCUCUCUGGCGAGCCCCCCGGCCGAUUCGGAGAGCCGGAUAGGGUAGGGCCGCAGAAGUUUCUGAGCGCGGCCAAGCCAGCAGGGGCCUCGGGCCUGAGCCCUCGGAUCGAGAUCACUCCGUCCCACGAACUGAUCCAGGCAGUGGGGCCCCUCCGCAUGAGAGACGCGGGCCUCCUGGUGGAGCAGCCGCCCCUGGCCGGGGUGGCCGCCAGCCCGAGGUUCACCCUGCCCGUGCCCGGCUUCGAGGGCUACCGCGAGCCGCUUUGCUUGAGCCCCGCUAGCAGCGGCUCCUCUGCCAGCUUCAUUUCUGACACCUUCUCCCCCUACACCUCGCCCUGCGUCUCGCCCAAUAACGGCGGGCCCGACGACCUGUGUCCGCAGUUUCAAAACAUCCCUGCUCAUUAUUCCCCCAGAACCUCGCCAAUAAUGUCACCUCGAACCAGCCUCGCCGAGGACAGCUGCCUGGGCCGCCACUCGCCCGUGCCCCGUCCGGCCUCCCGCUCCUCAUCGCCUGGUGCCAAGCGGAGGCAUUCGUGCGCCGAGGCCUUGGUUGCCCUGCCGCCCGGAGCCUCACCCCAGCGCUCCCGGAGCCCCUCGCCGCAGCCCUCAUCUCACGUGGCACCCCAGGACCACGGCUCCCCGGCUGGGUACCCCCCUGUGGCUGGCUCUGCCGUGAUCAUGGAUGCCCUGAACAGCCUCGCCACGGACUCGCCUUGUGGGAUCCCCCCCAAGAUGUGGAAGACCAGCCCUGACCCCUCGCCGGUGUCUGCCGCCCCAUCCAAGGCCGGCCUGCCUCGCCACAUCUACCCGGCCGUGGAGUUCCUGGGGCCCUGCGAGCAGGGCGAGAGGAGAAACUCGGCUCCAGAAUCCAUCCUGCUGGUUCCGCCCACUUGGCCCAAGCCGCUGGUGCCUGCCAUUCCCAUCUGCAGCAUCCCAGUGACUGCAUCCCUCCCUCCACUUGAGUGGCCGCUGUCCAGUCAGUCAGGCUCUUACGAGCUGCGGAUCGAGGUGCAGCCCAAGCCACAUCACCGGGCCCACUAUGAGACAGAAGGCAGCCGAGGGGCUGUCAAAGCUCCAACUGGAGGCCACCCUGUGGUUCAGCUCCAUGGCUACAUGGAAAACAAGCCUCUGGGACUUCAGAUCUUCAUUGGGACAGCUGAUGAGCGGAUCCUUAAGCCGCACGCCUUCUACCAGGUGCACCGAAUCACGGGGAAAACUGUCACCACCACCAGCUAUGAGAAGAUAGUGGGCAACACCAAAGUCCUGGAGAUACCCUUGGAGCCCAAAAACAACAUGAGGGCAACCAUCGACUGUGCGGGGAUCUUGAAGCUUAGAAACGCCGACAUUGAGCUGCGGAAAGGCGAGACGGACAUUGGAAGAAAGAACACGCGGGUGAGACUGGUUUUCCGAGUUCACAUCCCAGAGUCCAGUGGCAGAAUCGUCUCUUUACAGACUGCAUCUAACCCCAUCGAGUGCUCCCAGCGAUCUGCUCACGAGCUGCCCAUGGUUGAAAGACAAGACACAGACAGCUGCCUGGUCUAUGGCGGCCAGCAAAUGAUCCUCACGGGGCAGAACUUUACAUCCGAGUCCAAAGUUGUGUUUACUGAGAAGACCACAGAUGGACAGCAAAUUUGGGAGAUGGAAGCCACGGUGGAUAAGGACAAGAGCCAGCCCAACAUGCUUUUUGUUGAGAUCCCUGAAUAUCGGAACAAGCAUAUCCGCACACCUGUAAAAGUGAACUUCUACGUCAUCAAUGGGAAGAGAAAACGAAGUCAGCCUCAGCACUUUACCUACCACCCAGUCCCAGCCAUCAAGACGGAGCCCACGGAUGAAUAUGACCCCACUCUGAUCUGCAGCCCCACCCAUGGAGGCCUGGGGAGCCAGCCUUACUACCCCCAGCACCCGAUGGUGGCCGAGUCCCCCUCCUGCCUCGUGGCCACCAUGGCUCCCUGCCAGCAGUUCCGCACGGGGCUCUCAUCCCCUGACGCCCGCUACCAGCAACAGAACCCAGCGGCCGUACUCUACCAGCGGAGCAAGAGCCUGAGCCCCAGCCUGCUGGGCUAUCAGCAGCCGGCCCUCAUGGCCGCCCCGCUGUCCCUUGCGGACGCUCACCGCUCUGUGCUGGUGCACGCCGGCUCCCAGGGCCAGAGCUCAGCCCUGCUCCACCCCUCUCCGACCAACCAGCAGGCCUCGCCUGUGAUCCACUACUCACCCACCAACCAGCAGCUGCGCUGCGGAAGCCACCAGGAGUUCCAGCACAUCAUGUACUGCGAGAAUUUCGCACCAGGCACCACCAGACCUGGCCCGCCCCCGGUCAGUCAAGGUCAGAGGCUGAGCCCGGGUUCCUACCCCACAGUCAUUCAGCAGCAGAAUGCCACGAGCCAAAGAGCCGCCAAAAACGGACCCCCGGUCAGUGACCAAAAGGAAGUAUUACCUGCGGGGGUGACCAUUAAACAGGAGCAGAACUUGGACCAGACCUACUUGGAUGAUGACUUCACCGAUUUCACUCAUUCAGGGUUCCUAUCUGGACCCAUUAGGCGUUUGAAUUGUGCCCCCAUUACGGAAGUGCCACACAUAUCCAAGGCUCAUUAAUCCAGGACCUGCAUCCGGCCGGGGCCUUCGAAAGUGUUCCCUCCCUCUACCUUCCUUCCCCUCCUUGUGGCUGGGGAAGAUUUUUAAAUGGGGGUAAGAUUUUAAAACUUUUAAUUAAAUAUUUUGAACAUAUGUAACUAUAGCAUAGUACAAGGUACCCCUACAUACCCACCACGAGGCUUCAGCUGUUAUCAAUGCAUGGCCAAUCUGAUUUCUUCUACACCUUCAUCCUGUUAUAUUCAUUACCUGGUAAUUUUGUUUUGGGGGUUUGUUGUUAUUAGUUUUUUUUGUUUUUUUUUUUUUUUAAGACAUAGGGUCUUGCUAUGUUGCCCAGGCUGGAGCAUAGUGGCUAUUCACAGGUGUAAUCAUGGUGCACUGCAGUGUCGAUUUCCUGGGCUCAAACAAUCUUCCUGCCUCAGCCUCCAGCAUAGCUGGGACUGUAGGUGCCUGCUAUGGUGCCUAGCUACACAGCAAUAUUUUGAAGCAAAUCCUAGACAUCCUAUAAUUUCGUGUAGAAAUAGCAUGUAUCUCUAAAAAAAGGACUCUGAAAGUACAAGACCACUAGCACACAUGGAAAUUAAUAAUACUUCCUUAAUAUCAUGAAAUACCUAGUGUUUAAACUUCCGGUUGUCUUAUAUAUAAAUAUCAUAAAAGUGUUUUCUUCUUUGUUUUUAUUAUAGUUCAUUUGCGUCGGGAGUCAGACCAAGCGUUGCAAGCAGAUGCCUUUGUUUUAAGUCUGGUUUGAUGGGGAGGUUCUUCCCCUAGAUUAAAUCUAGAGGUUCUUCCUCUAGAUUAAAUAAUAAGAUCCUUUUUUGGUUUCAUCAUUAGUAUUAUAUUGCAAUUUAUUUGUUGAAAAAAUGAGGUUGUUUAUCCUGUGAAAUUUUUCAGUCUGGCUUUUGCCAGUUAUAUCUCCAUGAUGAGGUUUUUAGUGUGUUCCUGUCUCCUCUGUAUGUCCUGUAAGUUAGCAGUAAAACUGAGAGGCUUCAUUCAUUCAGAUUCAAUUGUUUUUGGCAAGAUUGCUUCAUGGGUGAUGACACAUCCUUCUGACAGGAGGUACGUGGAGUUGGGUUGCCUGUCUUUUGGUGAUAGUCAGUGCCUUGCUCCAUUAAUUCAGUGGUGCAUGAAUUAUAAAAUGGUGAUAUUCUAUUCUAAUUCUGCCAUCCCUUCCUCUACUGUUAGCUGGAAAACUUCUAUAAAGAGAAACUUUCCUUCAUCAACAAUGAUAGAAUUCAUAUAGGAAAAGCAGGAUGAAUGCUUGAUUCUUUCCCUUUAUUUACCAGUUUUUAAAAUAAUGGGUUGGUUCAUUAAUAUCUUACAGUGAUGAUCCAUUACGGUUGUUUGUGUGUAGUUGCUUUUUUUUUUUUUGGUACCAUUAUGAACUCAUGAAUUUAAGCAUAAUUGGUGUUUUAAGAUUUUAAUGGGCUUUUUUUUGGUAGUUCCUUUUGUCCUUAUCAUUUGAAGGACUGAAAUAAUAUGACUUCCUGUCCUUUCUUUCUCUGGCUUAGCAAUGUCCUCAGAUAUUCUGAAGCCUGAGGGAGGAAAUAAUCCUACAUGUGAACUGAGGAUCACAUCUCCUACACGUGAGAAGGGGAAAUCAUGAAAUCCCUCUCGAAUGCCAGCUGCUGAGAUACUCCUUGCGGUGUUAUGGAGUCUUUGAGCGUGAUUCCAAAGCAGUUAGUGCUUGCAAGGCAGGGGAGGUUAUUGGGAGGAUUAUUAGAGGGUAUUGAUUAGGAUGUAGAGGCUGCUGUAACCAAACCCAAAGUAACAAUGACUUUAACAAGAUAGAUGAUUUCUUCCUCUUGUAACAGCACAGGGAUAAGCAGUCCAUGGCUGGUAUGCUGGCCCCAUCAUACCAGGAACCCAGGCUUUUUCUGUCUUAUCACUCUCCAUUCUCAGGAUGGUACCCUCAUCUGAGUCAUCCAAGAUGGCUCCUGGAUGGGAAAAAAGAGGAAGGAGGGCACGCCCUUUCCUUUAAGGGCGUAACCCAGAAAUCACAUUUAUCCCUUCAGCUAAUACUGUAUUGGCCAGAGUCUUGUUAUGUAACCACACUGAGCCACAGAGGAGGCUGGGAAGUAUAGUUUUUAUAUUUAUAUUACCCAGUCAUGUGCAUAGCUGAAACCUGCUACUGUGGAAGACAGGAGAAUGGAUUUGGGGUCUUUGUGCAGGAUAGAUAUGAUCAUAAUGAGAAAACAGCUGCAAAAGGAGGUUGGAUAUUUUGUAUGACUUGAUAUUCUUAGGAGUUUCUUUAUUCCACAAAUAUUUAUUGAAUCCCUACUGUGUGCCAGUGAGGACACAGCAGCAUGUGAAACAGAGUCUCUGCCUUCAGGGAGCGUACUUCUUAGUUGGUGAGACAAACAGUGAAAUAAAUAUAUAUUAUAAUGUCAGGUGGUAAAUACGUACUAUAAAGAAAACCUAGGGCGGUGGGGGUGGCUCACGCCUAUAAUCCCAGCACUUUGGGAAGCCGAGGCAGGCAGAUCACUUAAGGUCAGUAGUUCAAGACCAGUCUGGCCCAACAUGGUGAAACCCCAUUUGUACUUAAAAUACAAAAAUUAGCUGGAUGUGGUGGCAUGCGCCUGUAAUCCCAGCUACUAGGGAAGCUGAGGCAGGAAAAUCCCUUGAACCUGGGAGGCAGAGGUUGCAGUGAGACGCAAUCGUACCACUGCACUCCAGCCUGGGGGACAGAGCGAGACUCCGUCUCAAAAAAAAAAAAAAAAAAAAACCAAACAAACAACAAAAGAAAACCUAAAACAGAAUGAGGGUGAGGCCUUAAAUGUCCAGUUAUUGCCAAUUUUCCCCAAAUUCAGGAAACUCCUCUCCUAACGGUCAGUCCAGGAAUCUCAAAACAUUUUCUUAUUACCUUUUCUCUUGAAGCAAGUCUUUCAGCUUCAGCACUACUGACAUUUCGGGCUGGAUUAUUCUCUGUUGUGAGGGGCUAUCCUGUGCAUGAAAGGAUGUGUACCAGCGUUCCUGGCCUCAAUGCACCGGAUGCCAGUAGCACCCCAGAUGUGGCCAUCAGAAAUGUCUGCAGAUACUGCCAAGUAUCCCCUGGGGGGCAGAGUUGCCCCUGGUUAAGAACCACCAUCUGAAGGAUUUAGUGUCCAGCUCUGGUAGAAGUAACAGCUUUAUAAUAUUGAGUGCUGACCACACCAUGUGUGUUUCGGGGAAGGAGUGUCCACUCUACAAAAAGAUUGUUACUGGUGGACUGGAGCAUUCCUAGCACUCUCUGAGUGUGGGAAGCCACCGGGAACUAGUGUCUCCCCAUGGCACCGCCUGUUCCCUAGUACAGCACCCAGGACAGGGGCCCCAGGGUCAGAAGAUGUUGCUGAGUAGUUAGUGUCAAAGGAAGCUUGAUUCAGAGCCUUCAUUCUUCCUUGCUUGUGGCCUUGGGCGAGGCAUGUGUGAAAAGUGACUUACGGACUGCCCGGUGCCCCGCGGGUACCAGGGAGGGCUGAUGCUGUGAUGUGGAUGCCGCCUCCUUUAGCAUUCAGCUGGCAGGCUGGCUGCCUCGGGAACUGCUCAGGGGGCGUGUUGCUGAGCAUUUGCUUUUUUGGUUUGUUUCUUAUCAACUGGUGUUCUUUCCUUCUUUGAACAGAUAUCCACUGAGUAUGUAAAGUGAGCUGGGCUUGGUGGUAGGUGCUGGGACACAGAAGUGAACCAAAUGGAUGGGGCCUCCCUGCUGGCAGAGCUUGCUCUGCAAGGGGAAGGCUGUUCAUCAAAUGUCAACCAGAAAAUGAUGAGAAUUUCAGAUGUUGGGGGUGGAGACUAAGUGCGGAGUUCAAUAAAGUGACGAUGGGGACGGGCAUAACUUCAAACGGGGUGGUCAGGACCAACCUCUUUGAGGAAGUGACUUUGGAUUUGAGACCGGGAGGAAGAGAGUGAGGGGAAGGAAUUCCAGGCAGAGGGAAGAGCAAGCACGUAGGGCAGAGCUGGGAGGAAACGUGGUUUGUGUGGAGGACAGAGAGAGGUCUGGUGUGGUUGAGAGUAAUGACGGCGGCGUCAUGGAAAGGGAGCAUGGAGGGGACAGGCCUCGCGGGUUGAGAGCUAUGGAUUUUAUUUUGGGAGGAAGGGGAAGCUACUGGCAGGUGGAAGGUUGAAGUUUUGGAGGGAGUGUGUUUGCCAGACUGACAAGUACAGGAAAUAUUGUAACAAUGCUAAUGAUCCCUCCCCCUUACUGGGCGCCGUGGAAGGCAGGGAUGGUCAUCUCUGCAUCUUAGAUGUGAAAGCAGGCUGAGAAAAGGGAGGGAUUUGUCUGAGGUUACAAAGCCAGAGGCACAGGCAAUGGGUGGUUAGAGGCACGUGUGUGAGAAGUGAUUCUGAGUCCACGUAUAAAGAGAAUAGGGCAUUUAUCCUGGGCUGCUCCCCCUGCCUUUUCACUCCUUCAUCUGAUGAGACUCCAGGAAACUGGCUUUUGCCCCAGACCCACUGAUCUGACCUCCUCCUGGGCCCUCCAUGUGGAUUCCCUGCAGGAACCUCACAUUCAACCAGCGCUAAAGUGAAUUCUUGCUACUGCCCCUACUGUCCCUCUGGCCCCCAUGCUCAGCUCCCAUCUGUUGCCUAAGGAACUUGGGGGUGUGGCCUUAGGUGAGUUACUGAAUGUCUGUGACCUCAAUUUCCCCAUCUGCAAAAUGGGGAUAUUAGCAGUGCUUGAGGUUUAAAGGAAAUGAUGUAUGAGAAGUGAGUAUAACCAGGUCAGCCACACAGCACUCCAUAGAGAGCAGCUAUCAGCUUCAUCAUCUUCUUAGCCUCAUCUUUAUCUGUCCAGGGCUGCAGAAAUGUCUUCAUCUCUGCACUUGGGAUGUGCCAACCCUCCUUUAAUAUCUUCUCACCAGUUUUUGGCCCCCACGUAGCCUCUCCCAGAUUUGAACGGGCCCUUUAUUCCAGACAGAUGUGAAACCCCUUCAUCAUGGCUUCCUGUUUGAGGGAGCAGCCCCUUCAGCCAGACAGAGUGAGAAGCCAGGAGCUGGCACCCUGGGAAUCCCAGGUGGGUGCUGUGCCCUACCCAGGCAGAGCCGGCAGGUCCUCUGAGUCCUGAGGGUCCUGGUCUGGUUCCUCUGUUUUCUCUCUGGACCAUUUCAGAACCAAUUCCCUCAGCUAUCUCUGGGAUUUUUUUAUUUUGAGACAGAGUCUCACUCUCUCUCUCUCAGACUGGAGUGCAGCGGUGUGAUCUCGGUUCGCUGCAACCUCUGCCUUCAGGGUUCAAGUGAUUCUCCUGCCUCAGUCUCCAGAGUAGCUGGGAUUACAGGAGUGUGCCACCAUGUCCGGAUAAUUUUUGUAUUUUUAGUAGAGACGGGGUCUCGCUUUGUUGGCCAGGCUGGUCUUGAACUCCUGACAUCAAGUGAUCCACCCACCUCGGCCUCCCAAAGUGCUGGGAUUACAGGCACGAGUCACCACACCUGGCAGCUAUCUCUGGGAUUUUUAAACUCCUACUGUUUUCUUUUUCCCUGGACUUCCUAUUAUCUGAACAUCAUUAUCUGUAUUUGGUGCAGGAUUGUUCCAGACCAGGGUCAGUUUUUCCUCCUGUGAGACUGACAACAUUGGCAAGAAAGAAAGGGAAAGGAGGAGGAGGAAUGGAAGGAAGGGAGGCUGAUAAAGUGCGGUAUUGGUGAGAGGGUGUGAAACAUGUCCUCUCAGUCAUUAUUGGUGGGCAUCUGCAUGGGUAGAACCUCUUUUGAAGGGCAAUUUGGUGAAAUGAACCCAAAUUUAGAAUGCACACAUCUUUUAAUCCAGAAUAUCCCACUUCUAGAAAUGUAUCUUUAGAGGUGUGCUGGCCCAGCUGUGAGCCAGGCUGGCUGUUGAUUCCAUGUCACUGGUCCCCAGCCCUGCACAGUGUUCUCUGGCAUGAAGCUUGGUGACUUCAGGAGCUCUUGGUUUUCCUGGAUCCCCAGAGACAGGUGGUGGCCAACUACUCAGGGACCACAAUAAGCCUCAUCUGUCUUCAGGAAGCCGGGUCCAUCCAGAUACCUGCUGCGUGUGGUGUGUGGGAUGUUGACUCCAGCCUUGUCUAUAGUAGCAGGAGACUAGAAACAGGCUAAAUGUCUGUUAAUAAGAUGCAGACACACAAGGAAAUACUGAGCAAGAGUAGAAGGGAGACUUUCUCCUGAUUGUGUUUUUAGAAUUUUUUUUUUUUUUUUUUGAUACAGGGUCUUACUCUGUCACUCAGGCUGGAGUGCCAUGGUAGGAUCAUGGCUCACUGCAGCCUCAAACUCCCAGGCCCAAGUGAUCCUCCCACCUCAGCUCCCCAAGUAGCUGGGAUUACCAGCAUGUGCCACCACACCUGGCUAGUUAUUUUUUGUAGAGAUGGGGUCUCACUAUGUUGCCCAGGCUGGUCUCAAAACUCCUGAGCUCAAGGAAUCCACCAACUUUGGCCUCCCAAAGUGCUGGGAUUACAGGCAUUAGCAACCAUGCCCAGCCCCUAGGAGAGAAUUUUUAAAAAGAAAGGGGCAGAUUUCAGGUCCUAGAAAUGACCCCAGAGGCUGGAGUGAAAAUGAGGAUUUAGAAACAGAAACCUUUCUGUUCUGGUUGGGGCUGUGUUUCCGGCUGUGUGUAUGCAUGAUCAGCCUCGCCCACCCCUCAGCUGUGAGGGGAGGAUGACUGCGGCUGUGCGGAGGCUUUCUUGCCUCCAAACCUUUGCCCAUGCCUUAACCACCGCCUGGAAAUCCUGCUCUCCUGUGACUUUUUUUUUUUCUUUUUUUAACAGAGUCUUGUUUUGUUGCCCA